AUAAUAGGAGCGCUUGGCCUCUGAGACUACCCGGCAGAAGGGACGUCCCCAAAUGACACUCGGAGGCCGCCUCCCUGGGCUCCGGUGCUCGGUGCCGGGAGGAGCGGCACGGCUUUCUACCCCGCCUCAGGUGCGCCAGCACGUUUUCUGGGCAGCAUCUGUGUGUUAGGCGACCGGAGAGGUGGGUUCCUUAUAGGGAAUAAGAAAACUGAAACUGACUUCCAACUGCAGGCAGAAGGAAGCAGUGGUCAUUGCUGGAGGUUAAAACUGUUCUGACCGGGCGCAGUGGCUCACGCCUGUAUUCCCAGCACUUUGGGAGGCUGAGGCGAGCAGAUCACGAAGUCAGGAGAUCAAGACCAUCCUGGCCAACAAGGUGAAACCCCGGCUCUACUAAAAAUACAAAAAUUAGCUGGGCGUGGUGGCGCGCGCCGGAAGUCCCAGCUACUUGGGAGGAUGAGGCAGAAGAAUCGCUUGAACCCGGGAGGCGGAGGUUGCGGUGAGCCGAGAUCGCGCCAUUGCACUCCAGCCUGGCGACUCAGCGAUACUCCGUCCCCCUCUCCCCGCCCCAAGAAAAAUCUGUUCAGUGGGGAGCGACAAGGAAGGAGCUUUCAGCCCGACUGGGGUCGCAGGGAAGAAUUCAAGAUGGCGUGUUUAGGAGCUCUAGCUCCUUGACAAAUUAGUAAAAUGUUAGUCUUAGGAGAAGAACGAAAAGGCUCUCCUAGGCUAAGAAACAGCAUACACAGUGAGAAACCUCAGAAGAAAUAAAAUUCAAGGAAGAUAGCAACAACGAAAACAUCAGAAGGAACACUAAAGUAGUCAAAUCAGCCUAGCAGAAACAAAGUACGUUAACCAAUGGAAAACUGACGGAGAGAAAUAAACUGUUUUUGCACAGCUAAAUGGAAAUGACUUUUGAAUUAUCUGCUUUGGAAGAUUAUCCAUGACACUGUUCUGCCCUGCUCUGCUCUAACAACAUUUGGAUUCACCUACGCUCUUACCAGCUGGAGGGAGUAAACUGGCUCGCCCAGCGCUUCCAUUGUCAGAAUGGCUGUAUCCUGGGAGAUGAGAUGGGCCUGGGGAAGACCUGCCAGACUAUUGCUCUCUUCAUUUAUUUGGCAGGAAGAUUAAAUGAUGAAGGGCCAUUUCUGAUUCUUUGUCCCUUGUCUGUUUUGAGCAACUGGAAAGAAGAAAUGCAGAGAUUUGCUCCAGGUCUUUCCUGUGUAACAUAUGCAGGCGACAAGGAGGAAAGAGCCUGCCUUCAGCAAGACCUGAAACAGGAGUCACGUUUUCAUGUGCUACUGACUACCUAUGAGAUUUGCUUGAAAGAUGCAUCAUUUCUAAAAUCAUUCCCUUGGAGUGUUCUUGUUGUGGAUGAAGCUCACAGGUUGAAAAACCAAAGCUCCCUGCUGCAUAAGACCUUGUCAGAGUUCUCAGUAGUCUUCAGUCUCCUGUUGACCGGAACUCCCAUCCAGAACAGCCUCCAAGAGCUCUACUCCCUCCUCAGUUUUGUGGAGCCUGAUCUCUUUUCCAAGGAAGAGGUGGGAGAUUUUAUUCAACGCUACCAGGAUAUUGAGAAAGAAUCUGAGUCAGCAAGUGAACUGCACAAACUCUUGCAGCCAUUUCUGCUGAGGCGAGUGAAAGCUGAGGUAGCUACAGAGCUUCCCAAGAAGACAGAAGUAGUGAUAUACCAUGGCAUGUCAGCAUUGCAGAAGAAAUACUACAAGGCCAUUUUGAUGAAAGACCUAGAUGCAUUUGAAAAUGAGACGGCAAAGAAAGUUAAACUACAGAACAUUUUGUCCCAGCUUCGAAAGUGUGUGGAUCACCCAUAUUUGUUUGAUGGUGUGGAGCCGGAGCCUUUUGAAGUUGGAGACCACCUGACUGAGGCUAGUGGGAAGCUUCACCUGCUGGAUAAGCUACUAGCAUUCCUGUAUUCUGGGGGCCAUCGGGUUUUACUUUUCUCCCAAAUGACCCAGAUGUUGGAUAUUCUCCAAGACUAUAUGGAUUACAGAGGCUACAGCUAUGAGCGUGUGGAUGGUUCUGUGAGAGGAGAAGAGAGACACUUGGCCAUUAAGAACUUUGGACAGCAGCCCAUUUUCGUUUUUCUCCUGAGUACUAGGGCAGGUGGAGUUGGCAUGAACUUAACAGCAGCAGAUACUGUGAUUUUUGUUGACAGUGACUUUAAUCCUCAGAAUGACUUGCAAGCAGCUGCCAGGGCUCAUCGCAUUGGCCAAAACAAGUCUGUUAAAGUUAUUCGGCUGAUUGGUCGAGACACUGUGGAAGAAAUAGUCUAUAGGAAAGCAGCCUCCAAACUGCAGCUCACCAACAUGAUCAUAGAAGGAGGCCAUUUUACUCUGGGAGCCCAGAAACCCGCUGCCGAUGCUGACCUCCAGUUGAGUGAGAUACUCAAAUUUGGUUUGGAUAAACUGCUGGCCUCUGAGGGGAGCACCAUGGAUGAAAUAGACCUGGAGUCCAUCCUGGGAGAAACAAAAGAUGGCCAGUGGGUCUCUGAUGCCUUGCCUGCAGCAGAAGGAGGGAGCAGAGAUCAAGAGGAAGGAAAAAAUCAUAUGUACUUAUUUGAAGGUAAAGAUUAUUCUAAAGAGCCCAGUAAGGAAGACAGAAAAUCAUUUGAACAACUGGUAAACCUUCAGAAAACCCUUUUGGAGAAAGCUAGUCAAGAGGGCCGAUCACUCCGAAAUAAAGGCAGUGUUCUCAUCCCAGGCCUUGUGGAGGGAUCUACCAAAAGGAAGCGGGUUCUGAGUCCAGAAGAGCUGGAGGACAGACAGAAGAAAAGACAAGAAGCAGCUGCCAAGAGAAGGAGACUCAUAGAGGAGAAGAAGAGGCAAAAGGAAGAGGCUGAACAUAAGAAAAAGAUGGCCUGGUGGGAAUCCAACAAUUACCAGUCCUUCUGCCUGCCCUCUGAGGAGAGCGAGCCAGAGGACCUUGAGAAUGGGGAAGAGAGCUCUGCUGAGCUGGAUUACCAAGACCCAGAUGCUACUUCCCUCAAGUACGUUAGUGGUGAUGUCACCCACCCUCAGGCUGGGGCCGAGGAUGCUCUCAUUGUGCACUGCGUAGAUGACUCUGGCCACUGGGGCAGAGGUGGUUUAUUUACAGCUCUGGAAAAGCGAUCCGCUGAGCCAAGAAAAAUAUAUGAGCUGGCUGGGAAAAUGAAAGACCUGAGUUUGGGAGGUGUCCUUUUAUUUCCUGUUGAUGAUAAAGAAUCAAGAAACAAAGGGCAAGAUUUGUUGGCCUUGAUUGUGGCUCAGCAUCGUGAUCGUUCCAAUGUCCUGUCUGGCAUUAAGAUGGCAGCCCUAGAAGAGGGCCUGAAGAAGAUAUUUUUAGCAGCAAAAAAGAAGAAAGCAAGUGUUCAUCUUCCACGUAUUGGACAUGCCACGAAAGGUUUUAACUGGUAUGGUACUGAGCGACUUAUUCGGAAACAUCUGGCUGCAAGAGGCAUCCCAACUUACAUAUAUUAUUUUCCUAGAAGCAAGUCUGCUGUCCUUCAUUCACAGUCUUCAUCUUCCUCCUCAAGACAGCUGGUGCCUUAAGAAUUGGCCCAGCCUCAGAUCCUGUCUUUAGCAACCAGCUAAUAUUUACCCAGAGGUACUGCAAUAGAGUAUUUCAAAAUGGAAUCAGGAUCUGGUGGGCCUCAGAAAUUGUCUCUUUUCUGAGUUUCAGUUUGGUUCUCCUGGAUGUUUUGCUCUGUUUUGGUACCUGUAAUAUAGGGAAACACAACUUUUUUUGGGAAAGCCCUUUGACCCCAGCUUGCUAGUUGCAUAAUAAUAAAUUUUCUGUUCCUAA